AUUUCCGGCUCCCUGUCACCGGGAGUGGGCGGGCCAUUUCUUGUUCUCUCUCCCGCUCUCGGAAGCUUUCGUCUCGUGGGUGCGAAAGGUAACCGAAGCGGCUCAGGAAGGCAGCUGUCACUGAGCCCCUGGAACAGAGCGAGAGUAUCCUUCCGGUUCCGGGGAGGGGCCGAGUUUUCUUCGAAGAUUUGGGGCUCCGCGAUACAGUUAGGAUGGCUGUAGUACCUCUGCUGUUGUUGGGGGGUUUGUGGAGCGCUGUGGGAGCGUCCAGCCUGGGUGUCGUUACUUGCGGCUCCGUGGUGAAGCUACUCAAUACGCGCCACAACGUCCGACUGCACUCACACGACGUGCGCUAUGGGUCAGGUAGUGGGCAGCAGUCAGUGACAGGUGUAACCUCUGUGGAUGACAGCAACAGUUACUGGAGGAUACGGGGGAAGAGUGCCACAGUGUGUGAGAGGGGAACCCCCAUCAAGUGUGGCCAGCCCAUCCGGCUGACACAUGUCAACACUGGCCGAAACCUCCAUAGUCACCACUUCACUUCACCUCUUUCUGGAAACCAGAGGAGAAAACAAAGGCUCAAAGGAUUUACAGAAGAAGGGAUCAAGUUGAGAUUCAAGGAAGUGAGUGCUUUUGGUGAGGAAGGUGAAGGUGAUUAUCUGGAUGACUGGACAGUGCUCUGUAAUGGACCCUACUGGGUGAGAGAUGGUGAGGUGCGGUUCAAACACUCUUCCACUGAGGUACUGCUGUCUGUCACAGGAGAACAAUAUGGUCGACCUAUCAGUGGGCAAAAAGAGGUGCAUGGCAUGGCCCAGCCAAGUCAGAACAACUACUGGAAAGCCAUGGAAGGCAUCUUCAUGAAGCCCAGUGAGUUGUUGAAGGCAGAAGCCCACCAUGCAGAGCUGUGAAUCUAGAGGCUCUGAGCCACUGUUAACGCACAAUGUUCACAGACAUCUGUUGCUGCCUCACCUUGGGAUCCCUGCCACAAGUUCCUUGGGCAGUGGCCAUGUCACCAUUGAGAUGAAGAUAUACAACAGAAAAUAGUGGCUGUGUUUGGAAGCUUCAGCCCUGCACAUUUGAACUAGUCACUCUCCCAGACUUGCGUGGGUCAGUUCUUUCUGAGUAGAGGACUUGCUGGUAAAGGGGCAGAUGCUUUUUAUUAGUACUGAUAAAACAAACUGAGGGAAACAUCCCUCUUAGCUGGGAAACUUUUACUCUUCAGGAGCUUGGCAUCAUGGACUGUUAAUGUAUGUGAUUUUCCCCCUAUUUUCUCUCUCCAAAAUGAUAAAAACAAUAAUUUUAUUAUGAGUCACUGUGUUGUUAUUUAUUAGGUGUGCUAUUUCAUUAGCUGCUUAAUCCUUUGAGUCCUAAGACUCUUUGGAGACGCUAUGAAGCUCCAAUGUGGGCCCUUUUAAGAGCUUUUCUUGCAUACAAACCUUUUCUCCCUCUACUUUGACUUCUCUCCAGGCAUCUCAUCUUUAAUAGAUCUUUGACUAAUUAUAGCUAAAAACUCUCAGAGAAUACAGCAUAAUAAAUAGCCAGUGAAAUGUU